AUGACUCUCUCUCUUGAGUAGGCACACACUCCCUUUUCUCGGGUGUGUACUUUUUGCUUUGUGAUACAUCUCUGCACUUUCAGUAUUUUCCAACUCAUCCUUAAAUUCCUUCUCACAACAGUGUCAAGAGCCUGGACGCCAGCCAGGAUUGAGGUCCUACGGGUGUUUGGGGACCUCCCCAAGCCCACGAGUAUCAAUGGCAGUAUCAAUUGUCUGUGACAGUGAUUAAGGAGCAAAACACUUGGCCUUCAUAUACCUGAAGAAAGUUUAAUUUGAAUACCUCAUUCUCAUCAUUUACCAUCCUCCCCACUCCCCCAUCCCCUGCCUUAAUAUUUCCUUUUUAAGGCAAAACAGUUUCCAUUUAGAAGCAAAGAAAGGGCUGACUCAAUGGACACCCACUGGUUGCUCCCCAGCCCUACUCCUCUCAAGGCAGUGGACAAGGCUCACGUGUUAGAAAGUGAAGGAACCCACAAGACUCCCAGAAGGUGAAGUUAAGAGCUCCCAGACUCAUAAGGUUAUUAGAACAGCAAACUGGCACCCCAAAGAACUUUACGGAGACUUGCAACCUAUCAACAAGUUGGAUGAGGGAUUAAAAGCCUUCAACAACCAACAACCCCAAGCAUCAAACUGAAGGAAACAUUCUAACCUUCACAGACAGACUGGAGGCUGGAUGGGGACCUGGCUGAAGACAUCUGGAGAAUGAAAGUUAAGUACCAGCUUGCAUUUUUGUGCCCCUAGAUUAUUUUUGCAUUUUAAAAUAAGAAGCAUCAAAUUGCGUGUCUCUGUGUAAAAGUUCUAGCAAUUUGUUUUAAGGUGAACUUAUUUUGGCUUAGGGACUACAAAAAGAGAAGGUAAUUCCUAGGGAAGGAAGAAGAGAAAGAAAUGAAAAUUAGAGAAUAAGAUUAUUUUGAAUGACUUCAGGUAGCGAGGAGUGUGUGUUUGUGAGUGUGUAUUUGAGAGACUUGGCUCAUGCCUGUGGGUCUUCUCUUCUAGUAUCAGUGAGGGGAGGGAUUACUGAAGAAGAAGGGGGGAAAAAAAAAGAAAGAAAUCUGAGCUUUCUGGGAGGAAAUUCAAAGGAACCAAGAGAAAUUAACUUCGUUCUGCAAGGACUAAAGUACAGCAAGAGGAGAGAGGUCAAGCGAGAAGCGUGCGGGAAGCACAUGCCCUGGGGAGGCAUAGAAGCCACACUGGCAGAGCGGCCAGCACAGGUAGCCAGCAGAGGCAUUCUUGGGGCUAUUUGAAAAAGUUUGGUCUGUGAACAAAACAGUUUCCCUGGUGACUGCAAAUCCAUUGCUAGCUGCCUCUUUCUCGUCUGCCCAUCACUCUGGUGUGGUACCCAGAAGUUGACUUCUGGUUCUGUAGAAAGAGCUAGGGGAGGUAUGAUGUGCUUAAAGAUCCUAAGAAUAAGCCUGGCGAUUUUGGCUGGGUGGGCACUCUGUUCUGCCAACUCUGAGCUGGGCUGGACACGCAAGAAAUCCUUGGUUGAGAGGGAACACCUGAAUCAGGUGCUGUUGGAAGGAGAACGUUGUUGGCUGGGGGCCAAGGUUCGAAGACCCAGAGCUUCUCCACAGCAUCACCUCUUUGGAGUCUACCCCAGCAGGGCUGGGAACUACCUAAGGCCCUACCCCGUGGGGGAGCAAGAAAUCCAUCAUACAGGACGCAGCAAACCAGACACUGAAGGAAAUGCUGUGAGCCUUGUUCCCCCAGACCUGACUGAAAAUCCAGCAGGACUGAGGGGUGCAGUUGAAGAGCCGGCUGCCCCAUGGGUAGGGGAUAGUCCUAUUGGGCAAUCUGAGCUGCUGGGAGAUGAUGACGCUUAUCUCGGCAAUCAAAGAUCCAAGGAGUCUCUAGGUGAGGCCGGGAUUCAGAAAGGCUCAGCCAUGGCUGCCACUACUACCACCGCCAUUUUCACAACCCUGAACGAACCCAAACCAGAGACCCAAAGGAGGGGCUGGGCCAAGUCCAGGCAGCGUCGCCAAGUGUGGAAGAGGCGGGCGGAAGAUGGGCAGGGAGACUCCGGUAUCUCUUCACAUUUCCAACCUUGGCCCAAGCAUUCCCUUAAACACAGGGUCAAAAAGAGUCCACCGGAGGAAAGCAACCAAAAUGGUGGAGAGGGCUCCUACCGAGAAGCAGAGACCUUUAACUCCCAAGUAGGACUGCCCAUCUUAUACUUCUCUGGGAGGCGGGAGCGGCUGCUGCUGCGUCCAGAAGUGCUGGCUGAGAUUCCCCGGGAGGCGUUCACAGUGGAAGCCUGGGUUAAACCGGAGGGAGGACAGAACAACCCAGCCAUCAUCGCAGGUGUGUUUGAUAACUGCUCCCACACUGUCAGUGACAAAGGCUGGGCCCUGGGGAUCCGCUCAGGGAAGGACAAGGGAAAGCGGGAUGCUCGCUUCUUCUUCUCCCUCUGCACCGACCGCGUGAAGAAAGCCACCAUCUUGAUUAGCCACAGUCGCUACCAACCAGGCACAUGGACCCAUGUGGCAGCCACUUACGAUGGACGGCACAUGGCCCUGUAUGUGGAUGGCACUCAGGUGGCUAGCAGUCUAGACCAGUCUGGUCCCCUGAACAGCCCCUUCAUGGCAUCUUGCCGCUCUUUGCUCCUGGGGGGAGACAGCUCUGAGGAUGGGCACUAUUUCCGUGGACACCUGGGCACACUGGUUUUCUGGUCGACCGCCCUGCCACAAAGCCAUUUUCAGCACAGUUCUCAGCAUUCAAGUGGGGAGGAGGAAGCGACUGACUUGGUCCUGACAGCGAGCUUUGAGCCUGUGAACACAGAGUGGGUUCCCUUUAGAGAUGAGAAGUACCCACGACUUGAGGUUCUCCAGGGCUUUGAGCCAGAGCCUGAGAUUCUGUCGCCUUUGCAGCCCCCACUCUGUGGGCAAACAGUCUGUGACAAUGUGGAAUUGAUCUCCCAGUACAAUGGAUACUGGCCCCUUCGGGGAGAGAAGGUGAUACGCUACCAGGUGGUGAACAUCUGUGAUGAUGAGGGCCUAAACCCCAUUGUGAGUGAGGAGCAGAUUCGUCUGCAGCACGAGGCACUGAAUGAGGCCUUCAGCCGCUACAACAUCAGCUGGCAGCUGAGCGUCCACCAGGUCCACAAUUCCACCCUGCGACACCGGGUUGUGCUUGUGAACUGUGAGCCCAGCAAGAUUGGCAAUGACCAUUGUGACCCCGAGUGUGAGCACCCACUCACAGGCUAUGAUGGGGGUGACUGCCGCCUGCAGGGCCGCUGCUACUCCUGGAACCGCAGGGAUGGGCUCUGUCACGUGGAGUGUAACAACAUGCUGAACGACUUUGACGACGGAGACUGCUGCGACCCCCAGGUGGCUGAUGUGCGCAAGACCUGCUUUGACCCUGACUCACCCAAGAGGGCAUACAUGAGUGUGAAGGAGCUGAAGGAGGCCCUGCAGCUGAACAGUACUCACUUCCUCAACAUCUACUUUGCCAGCUCAGUGCGGGAAGACCUUGCAGGUGCUGCCACCUGGCCUUGGGACAAGGACGCUGUCACUCACCUGGGUGGCAUUGUCCUCAGCCCAGCAUAUUAUGGGAUGCCUGGCCACACCGACACCAUGAUCCAUGAAGUGGGACAUGUUCUGGGACUCUACCAUGUCUUUAAAGGAGUCAGUGAAAGAGAAUCCUGCAAUGACCCCUGCAAGGAGACAGUGCCAUCCAUGGAAACGGGAGACCUCUGUGCCGACACCGCCCCCACUCCCAAGAGUGAGCUGUGCCGGGAACCAGAGCCCACUAGUGACACCUGUGGCUUCACUCGCUUCCCAGGGGCUCCGUUCACCAACUACAUGAGCUACACGGAUGAUAACUGCACUGACAACUUCACUCCUAACCAAGUGGCCCGAAUGCAUUGCUAUUUGGACCUAGUCUAUCAGCAGUGGACUGAAAGCAGAAAGCCCACCCCCAUCCCCAUUCCACCUAUGGUCAUCGGACAGACCAACAAGUCCCUCACUAUCCACUGGCUGCCUCCUAUUAGUGGAGUUGUAUAUGACAGGGCCUCAGGCAGCUUGUGUGGCGCUUGCACUGAAGAUGGGACCUUUCGUCAGUAUGUGCACACAGCUUCCUCCCGGCGGGUGUGUGACUCCUCAGGUUAUUGGACCCCAGAGGAGGCUGUGGGGCCUCCUGAUGUGGAUCAGCCCUGCGAGCCAAGCUUACAGGCCUGGAGCCCUGAGGUCCACCUGUACCACAUGAACAUGACGGUCCCCUGCCCCACAGAAGGCUGUAGCUUGGAGCUGCUCUUCCAACACCCGGUCCAAGCCGACACCCUCACCCUGUGGGUCACUUCCUUCUUCAUGGAGUCCUCGCAGGUCCUCUUUGACACAGAGAUCUUGCUGGAAAACAAGGAGUCAGUGCACCUGGGCCCCUUAGACACUUUCUGUGACAUCCCACUCACCAUCAAACUGCACGUGGAUGGGAAGGUGUCGGGGGUGAAAGUCUACACCUUUGAUGAGAGGAUAGAGAUUGAUGCAGCACUCCUGACUUCUCAGCCCCACAGUCCCUUGUGCUCUGGCUGCAGGCCUGUGAGGUACCAGGUUCUCCGCGAUCCCCCAUUUGCCAGUGGUUUGCCCGUGGUGGUGACACAUUCUCACAGGAAGUUCACGGACGUGGAGGUCACACCUGGACAGAUGUAUCAGUACCAAGUUCUAGCUGAAGCUGGAGGAGAACUGGGAGAAGCUUCGCCUCCUCUGAACCACAUUCAUGGAGCUCCUUAUUGUGGAGAUGGGAAGGUGUCAGAGAGACUGGGAGAAGAGUGUGAUGAUGGAGACCUUGUGAGCGGAGAUGGCUGCUCCAAGGUGUGUGAGCUGGAGGAAGGUUUCAACUGUGUAGGAGAGCCAAGCCUUUGCUACAUGUAUGAGGGAGAUGGCAUAUGUGAACCUUUUGAGAGAAAAACCAGCAUUGUAGACUGUGGCAUCUACACUCCCAAAGGAUACUUGGAUCAAUGGGCUACCCGGGCUUACUCCUCUCAUGAAGACAAGAAGAAGUGUCCUGUUUCCUUGGUAACUGGAGAACCUCAUUCCCUAAUUUGCACAUCAUACCAUCCAGAUUUACCCAACCACCGUCCCCUAACUGGCUGGUUUCCCUGUGUUGCCAGUGAAAAUGAAACUCAGGAUGACAGGAGUGAACAGCCAGAAGGUAGCCUGAAGAAAGAGGAUGAGGUUUGGCUCAAAGUGUGUUUCAAUAGACCAGGAGAGGCCAGAGCAAUUUUUAUUUUUUUGACAACUGAUGGCCUAGUUCCCGGAGAGCAUCAGCAGCCGACAGUGACUCUCUACCUGACCGAUGUCCGUGGAAGCAACCACUCUCUUGGAACCUAUGGACUGUCAUGCCAGCAUAAUCCACUGAUUAUCAAUGUGACCCAUCACCAGAAUGUCCUUUUCCACCAUACCACCUCAGUGCUGCUGAAUUUCUCAUCCCCACGGGUCGGCAUCUCAGCUGUGGCUCUAAGGACAUCCUCCCGCAUUGGUCUUUCGGCUCCCAGUAACUGCAUCUCAGAGGACGAGGGGCAGAAUCAUCAGGGACAGAGCUGUAUCCAUCGGCCCUGUGGGAAGCAGGACAGCUGUCCGUCAUUGCUGCUUGAUCAUGCUGAUGUGGUGAACUGUACCUCUAUAGGCCCAGGUCUCAUGAAGUGUGCUAUCACUUGUCAAAGGGGAUUUGCCCUUCAGGCCAGCAGUGGGCAGUACAUCAGGCCCAUGCAGAAGGAAAUUCUGCUCACAUGUUCUUCUGGGCACUGGGACCAGAAUGUGAGCUGCCUUCCCGUGGACUGCGGUGUUCCCGACCCGUCUUUGGUGAACUAUGCAAACUUCUCCUGCUCAGAGGGAACCAAAUUUCUGAAACGCUGCUCAAUCUCUUGUGUCCCACCAGCCAAGCUGCAAGGACUGAGCCCAUGGCUGACAUGUCUUGAAGAUGGUCUCUGGUCUCUCCCUGAAGUCUACUGCAAGUUGGAGUGUGAUGCUCCCCCUAUUAUUCUGAAUGCCAACUUGCUCCUGCCUCACUGCCUCCAGGACAACCACGACGUGGGCACCAUCUGCAAAUAUGAAUGCAAACCAGGGUACUAUGUGGCAGAAAGUGCAGAGGGUAAAGUCAGGAACAAGCUCCUGAAGAUACAAUGCCUGGAAGGUGGAAUCUGGGAGCAAGGCAGCUGCAUUCCUGUGGUGUGUGAGCCACCCCCUCCUGUGUUUGAAGGCAUGUAUGAAUGUACCAAUGGCUUCAGCCUGGACAGCCAGUGUGUGCUCAACUGUAACCAGGAACGUGAAAAGCUUCCCAUCCUCUGCACUAAAGAGGGCCUGUGGACCCAGGAGUUUAAGUUGUGUGAGAAUCUGCAAGGAGAAUGCCCACCACCCCCCUCAGAGCUGAAUUCUGUGGAGUACAAAUGUGAACAAGGAUAUGGGAUUGGUGCAGUGUGUUCCCCAUUGUGUGUAAUCCCCCCCAGUGACCCCGUGAUGCUACCUGAGAAUAUCACUGCUGACACUCUGGAGCACUGGAUGGAACCUGUCAAAGUCCAGAGCAUUGUGUGCACUGGCCGGCGUCAAUGGCACCCAGACCCCGUCUUAGUCCACUGCAUCCAGUCAUGUGAGCCCUUCCAAGCAGAUGGUUGGUGUGACACUAUCAACAACCGAGCCUACUGCCACUAUGACGGGGGAGACUGCUGCUCUUCCACACUCUCCUCCAAGAAGGUCAUUCCAUUUGCUGCUGACUGUGACCUGGAUGAGUGCACCUGCCGGGACCCCAAGGCAGAAGAAAAUCAGUAACUGUGGGAACAAGCCCCUCCCUCCACUGCCUCAGAGGCAGUAAGAAAGAGAGGCCGACCCAGGAGGAAACAAAGGGUGAAUGAAGAAGAACAAUCAUGAAAUGGAAGAAGGAGGAAGAGCAUGAAGGAUCUUAUAAGAAAUGCAAGAGGAUAUUGAUAGGUGUGAACUAGUUCAUCAAGUAGCCCAAGUAGGAGAGAAUCAUAGGCAAAAGUUUCUUUAAAGUGGCAGUUGAUUAACAUGGAAGGGGAAAUAUGAUAGAUAUAUAAGGACCCUCCUCCCUCACUUAUAUUCUAUUAAAUCCUAUCCUCAACUCUUGCCCUGCUCUCCGCUCCACCCCCUGCCAACUACUCAGUCCCACCCAACUUGUAAACCAAUACCAAAAUACUAGAGGAGAAGUUGGCAGGGAUACUGUUAAUACCCAUUUUGAAUGGAUUGCCAUCUUUCAGAGCUUGUCUGCUCUCAACUGGCUCUUUUUCUUUUUGUGUAGUUUCCCUUAAAUAAUGAAGUUAGUUAUUAAUUCUUUAUAAGUAUUUAAACAUAAUUAUAUAAAUAUAUUAUAUAUAUUAUAUUUUUUGCUGUUUACUAAGCUAAAAAUUAUUCAUUGUUCCACACAUGCUGCUGUGAAGUUCACAUUCAAGAUGAAUGUUGAGACUUUGAGGACAGAAAGGCAACUUAUUUUCCCAUCUUUCUAUGGAUGCGGAUUGGCAGGUUGAAUGGGAAGUACAGAAGGAGAGAGAGUAAUUAGAUGGAAUUCUGGAUGCUAGCAUGUAAAGCUAAUCAUCUUUUUUUUUAUGACCUGGGAGCUGGGCCCAUUUUAUGACCAAGGAGAUGGGGAGUUGGAAUGGUGGUACUAAGAGGCAUAGGAAGUUGAGUGUGAAUACCAUUGGUGAUGGGUCCAGGAGAACUAGACUAUGGUUCUUGAAUAUCUGUCCACAAAGAAUAUACUAACUUUUGUCAACUUCUCAGAACUCCCAACUGGAGUCGGUGAGACCUAGGAUUUUCUGCACUUCCACACAUGCCUGUUCCAAGUGUGGCUGUCAGCCAGUCAACAAGUUUGUACUAUGGCCCAUUCUCUGAUCACCAGGAUUACAGGAACUCACACACUCCUCAUACUUGGCCUGUAGUCCUACUUCUUGUUAGAAGUCUCCAAGUCUGGCCAGUCACAUGACCAAGUGUUGAUUUUUCUGGAGGAAAAAUUUUAUGGAAAUGAUAUAGGGGAAAGGUGGGAGGAGAUGAAAGAACAGGCAAGAGCUGUCAGGGUUAAAUCCAGGCCCGGGCAUGAGAAUGGAAGUGAUCAGGGAGACUCGGUCCUUGUUCCAAGUCUCCAAAGAAGACCAAAGUGGGUCCCUUGAGCAAUGAAGAAUCUGAGAUAAAUUCUCUUCAAGUAUCAUGUACAAAAUCUGUGAGCCAGAGAUUUUGACUUGAGCAAGCCAUGGAAAUGCAUGGAGCAAGGGUGACACUCUGUGGGGAGACAGAAGAAUUUCAACUAUUUAAUGUCCAUUUUGUUGUUUUUACCCUUUCUUAUCCAAUAGAUGGAAUGCACAUGAAAUGACCAUAUUAAGCCUCUCUCUAUUUACAUCCCAGGCUCACUGGGAUGUGAUCUACUGCAGUUACAUUUUCUUGUAACGGUUUCUGGAUUAGACCCUAGGGAAAGUGAGUAAGGAGCCAGUUUCUGUUUAACAUUCUAGUUUUACUCAUUUUAGGAAGGCUGUGAGUGAGGCUUGUCUCCUUUAAAGUUUCUUCUCCAAUGGAAACCAAGAACAGACAAAAUUUAGAGCUCAGCUGUGGUCUCUUCUCAUCUUCUGCUCUUUUGCUUUGACCACAGUUUUUCUACUCUUCCCAUCAACACUAGAGCAAUGGCUGUGCAAAUAGGAAUAGGAAAUACUACCACAAUGAUAGAAAUAUUAUCCACACUAUCACGUAGGGAAGAACAAUAUCCUGAAAGAGAAUAAAACACGAAUAAGGUGAUGUACCCACAUUAAUCUGUGGGUUUGUGGAAUGAGGGUUGCAAAGUUAUUGGGAAAAGGAAAGAGCAGAGUUCACCCAUUCAAAAAAAACCUUUUGUCUACUAAUCUCUAGUGUAAAGAAAAUGUAGUUCAGAUACCAUUCAUUGUCUUGGGUCAUGCUUAGUGCCCCCAAGAAGACAAACAUAUUUAUUCUUGGGAUUCUGAUAGGCUUCAAUAUGCAAAGGACAAUGGAAAAGUUUAGACACUCUAUUUUCAAAAUUUUAUAAACUUGUUUUAUUGGGGAAAAUGUCCAAAUUGCUAGACACAUUCUAAGUUCUGCCUUGGAGAAUCCUACUUUGUCUGAGAUUGAGGCAGAGGAAUUGUUAUCCUGGGCAUUACUCAGCUCAGGAACAUGGAGCCUGUGGUUCAUGCCAGUGUGUGUCUUCAUGCAGUCUCUCCACAAGAGCAACAGUAAGAACAUUUCUGUUUUAAAUUUCAUUUUAAAAUAUUUUAUUAUCUGCAAUUCACCACUGCUCUGGGAAAGCAAAAGGAAAGUUCCUGUUGUGUGUGAAGAGCCUCUUAGGCUAUAAGGCUUCCCAGCCAUAGUCAGCUAUAGCUAUUCAGAGACAGCAGGUUCUUCCAGUCUUUGUUCCUGGGACCUGAUGUUUUGAGCAACUCAGGUCACUGAUAAAGUGGAAGGACUAAGACACUGUGGUCACAGAUCCCAGCAACAUCAACUCACACUCAAUCCAUGUGGUGGUCCACAUUCUGCUACUCUUAUCCACCCAUGUGGUCAUUGAGAGCCUUUCUCAGAGACUCUUCUGUGUGUUUGAUUGUGCCCAGGUGGCCCAGGGCUAGCUGGCUCUAACAACUAGCAUGACAGCCUCCAAUCAGAAAGGCAGGUAAGGGGACAGGGUGAGGAGAAUGGGCAGAUACUGACAGAAAUUAAAGUAAAGGGAUUGUGAAAGUAAAGAGCUCUUCCUGAUUCUCAUCUUCUCUUUUUUCUAUUACAAGGCAUUGAACUUGGCACUUCCUGUAUUCUUUGUGAUCACUAUUGAGUGCAUUAGUUAACACCCAAGGGGAUGGCUUGAUUGGGAAUGUAGUGAAAGGAGCUGAUCUACUGUAUUGUAAUGUAAAACAGCUACAGCCAGUUAUUUUGUAAGAUUAUAAGUUGUUCAUUAAAAAAUCAGCACACAAAAUA